AGUGUUUGAUAAAGACAGCUCCUCUUAGGAAGAACUGUCAUCCCCAAACACAUAGAGAGACACUCUCUGUCUCUCGAUUACAAUCAUGAUUUCCAGAAUGGAGAAGAUGACGAUGAUGAUGAAGAUAUUGAUUAUGUUUGCUCUUGGAAUGAACUACUGGUCUUGCUCAGGUUUCCCAGUGUACGACUACGAUCCAUCCUCCUUAAGGGAUGCCCUCAGUGCCUCUGUGGUAAAAGUGAAUUCCCAGUCACUGAGUCCGUAUCUGUUUCGGGCAUUCAGAAGCUCAUUAAAAAGAGUUGAGGUCCUAGAUGAGAACAACUUGGUCAUGAAUUUAGAGUUCAGCAUCCGGGAGACUACAUGCAGGAAGGAUUCUGGAGAAGAUCCCGCUACAUGUGCCUUCCAGAGGGACUACUAUGUGUCCACAGCUGUUUGCAGAAGCACCGUGAAGGUAUCUGCCCAGCAGGUGCAGGGCGUGCAUGCUCGCUGCAGCUGGUCCUCCUCCACGUCUGAGUCUUACAGCAGCGAAGAGAUGAUUUUUGGGGACAUGUUGGGAUCUCAUAAAUGGAGAAACAAUUAUCUAUUUGGUCUCAUUUCAGACGAGUCCAUAAGUGAACAAUUUUAUGAUCGGUCACUUGGGAUCAUGAGAAGGGUAUUGCCUCCUGGAAACAGAAGGUACCCAAACCACCGGCACAGAGCAAGAAUAAAUACUGACUUUGAGUAACGGCCUUGAGAACAUCAUGGGUUAUGGGCAGGGAGAAUAGAGUUCUCAAUGGAUUGGCUGUAUUUUGUUUAUUAGUAAUAUGAUAACGUUGGAUGUGUAUACAUAUGUGUAUUGCAAUAUAAAUUCAUCAUUUGAUUUUUAUGAAGAAAUUGAUCACUCAAAACAUUUAUUUUUAAAGACAGCUGCAGCCCUGACCUGAACAUUGGAUUUGACUGAAGUCCCAGUUAUGUCUCUGCCCUCCCAUGACCUUUAGCAGGGCAGGUUUCUACACUGUGCUGGGUUCCCUGAAAUCACAGAAUGAGGCUGGUAAGGCCGGCAUAGUGGGUCUAGUGAGGAGGUCAAUCCGAUGGGAUCUGGAAUCCACGGGCCUGGUUCUGAGCCUGCUCUCCCAUCUGUAAUGGUGAUUCAGUUCCUUAACCUCUCAGGGUGCAAUUCCUUCAAGGGUUUAUUAUUACUUUUUGCUUUUUCUUGUCCAUACUAGACCAUAAGCUUCCUUUUUAUUUUGAGACAGAGUGUUGCUGUGUUGCCCAGGCUGGAGUGCAGUGGCACAAUCUCUGCUCACUGAAAACUCCGCCUCCCAGGUUCAAGCGAUUCUCCUGCCUCAGCCUCGUGAGUAGCUGGGAUUGCAGGUGCCCACCACCACGCCCAGCUAAUUUUUGUAUUUUUAGUAGAGAUGGGGUUUCACCAUGUUGGCCAGGCUAGUCUCAAACUCCUGACCUCAAGUGCUCCACCUGCCUUGGCCUCCCGAAGUGCUGGGAUUACAGGCAUGAGCCACCACGCCUGGCCGACCAUAAACUUCUUGAGGAUGCAUUCUCCUUGUUAAUUAUUGCAGUUUUACAACAUGUAAAAAUAUUAUUAAUGAUAUGUCUAUACAAAAUUAUUAAAAAUAUCUUUUGUCCAUUUCA